GGGGCGCGCGACUGCUCCGGGCGGCGAUGGCGGCGGACGGGGACUGGCAGGAUUUCUAUGAGUUCCAGGAGCCGGCCCGGAGCCUCCUGGACCAGGAGAACUGUAACGCGAGCCCCGAGCCUGGGGCGGAGGCGGGGGCCGAGGCGGGUGGGGGCGCCGACGGUUUCCCGGCCCCGGCCUGCAGCUUGGAGGAGAAGCUGAGCCUGUGCUUCCGCCCCUCGGAUCCGGGCGCCGAGCCCCCGAGGACGGCCGUGCGGCCCAUCACGGAGCGCAGCCUCCUGCAGGGGGACGAGAUUUGGAAUGCCCUGACAGAUAAUUAUGGGAAUGUGAUGCCUGUAGACUGGAAGUCAUCGCAUACUAGGACCUUGCACUUGCUUACUCUGAACCUCUCAGAAAAAGGGGUAAGUGACAGUUUGCUCUUUGAUACAUCAGAUGAUGAAGAGCUGAGAGAACAGCUGGAUAUGCACUCAAUCAUCGUCUCCUGUGUUAAUGAUGAACCCCUCUUCACGGCAGACCAGGUUAUUGAAGAAAUUGAAGAAAUGAUGCAGGAAUCACCGGACCCAGAAGAUGAUGAAACCCCUACACAGUCAGAUCGGCUUUCAAUGCUUUCCCAGGAAAUUCAAACUCUCAAGAGGUCUAGUACCGGCAGUUAUGAAGAGAGAGUGAAAAGGCUCUCAGUGUCUGAGUUAAAUGAAAUCCUGGAAGAAAUUGAGACUGCCAUUAAGGAGUACUCUGAGGAGCUGGUGCAGCAGUUGGCUUUACGAGAUGAACUGGAGUUUGAAAAGGAAGUGAAAAACAGCUUUAUUUCUGUUCUUAUUGAAGUGCAAAACAAACAGAAAGAGCACAAAGAAACAGCAAAAAAGAAAAAGAAACUAAAAAAUGGCAGCUCUCAGAAUGGGAAGAAUGAGAGAAGUCAUAUGCCCGGCACACGCUUCAGCAUGGAAGGGAUCUCAAAUGUCAUUCAGAAUGGCCUCCGCCACACCUUUGGAAAUUCAGGUGGAGAGAAACAGUAUUUGACUACAGUCAUUCCUUAUGAGAAAAAAAACGGACCACCGUCUGUUGAAGAUCUUCAAAUAUUAACAAAAAUUCUUCGUGCCAUGAAGGAGGACAGUGAAAAAGUUCCGAGCUUGUUAACUGAUUAUAUUCUGAAAGUUCUGUGUCCUACAUAGAGCAGCAACUUUAUCUGCGGUGGGCUCCAAGCUAGAUUUCCGACAGCAUUAUUCUGAGAGCUGGCUACCAUUACCCUUCUUGCUAUUGGAAACUCAGCACAUUUGAACUUGGGUUUGAUUCAGUAUUAACAGAUCUUGACUACACUAAUUCUUUAUAUUAUAGAACCAACGGAAAUAUGGGCACUAUUUUGAAUUCUAGAGAUGGUUUUUGUUAAAUCUACUAAUAAACUGUUCUCUUAGUAGAUUAAGAGAGAGUAAUAUUAAUUGUGCAUGUGCAGUUGUAUUUCUCAUUAACUGACAGUAUGCCCAUUUGUUUUUAUGGCUUUCUUAUCUAAACUGCACUGAUGAACUAGAUUAAAGCCUUGGGAGAUUUAUACUAUAAAUUCAGUGAUGGCAAGAACCAACACUGUUUUUUUGUGAGAAUUGUCAGUGUAACUAUUACCUACCAGUAUUGUUCAGAGAGAUUGAAACAGAAUAAACGGGCUGUUCUUGAAGAAGCAAAACCAGAAUAUGCAUUACUUUGGUUUAAUACUUAGUGCUAACAUUGAAACUGUUGGUGGUGAUGGAUUUUGUAGCUUGCUGCUUGUUUCACCACUGGUCAAAUUUUAACCAUUAAAUUGCCAUUCACUUUUAGAAUCUUGUAUUUAAGUUUUGAUUUUCAAAUGUUCUGCUUCAUGUGUCUGUGAAGAAUUGUACUUUAAGUGUGUGUCCUCUGAGGUGCUUGAGAAAGUGUACACUGCAGAACUGCCCAUUCUCAUUACUGUGUCCUAUUUUAUUCAUGCCUGUGUGUUUUUCUUAAGUAUGAAUUCUAGAUACAGCUACUUAUGGAUUCAUCAAUAUCAUGAGCACUUUUGCUGGUUCCAGUCAAAUCAAUGGCAUUUAAUAAAUUUUUUAAGAAGUAAAAA